AGUGGAGACGCGCCUUCUCGGCUCUGGUCCGCGCCCUGGGGCCCUGGCCUCCCUGGAGGGGCUGGGGAACUGGAAGCUGGGCCGAGAGAGUUCCCGCUGCAGCUAUCGCGCAGUCCCUCCUGCGCCCGGGCGCCCCCAGCGGGUUCCGGGAGGCGCCCGGUGAGCCCACGUCUGUUGCGGCGGAGCGAGCGCGCUCCGGGAGGGCCGAGAGCCGGCGGGGCUGGCAGGAGCUCUCGGGCGCCCGCCUCCCUCCUUCGCGGACGGUCUCCCGACACGCCGGCUGAGAGCCCUUUUCGACUGUGAGCUGCGGCAGCUGAGCAGAGGCGGCGGCGCGGGACCUGCAGUCGCCAGGGAUUCCCUCCAGGUGACGAUGCUCUGGUUCUCCGGCGUCGGGGCUCUGGCUGAGCGUUACUGCCGCCGCUCGCCUGGGAUUACGUGCUGCGUCUUGCUGCUACUCAAUUGCUCGGGGGUCCCCAUGUCUCUGGCUUCCUCCUUCUUGACAGGUUCUGUUGCAAAAUGUGAAAAUGAAGGUGAAGUCCUCCAGAUUCCAUUUAUCACAGACAACCCUUGCAUAAUGUGUGUCUGCUUGAACAAGGAAGUGACAUGUAAGAGAGAGAAGUGCCCCGUGCUGUCCCGAGACUGUGCCCUGGCCAUCAAGCAGAGGGGAGCCUGUUGUGAACAGUGCAAAGGUUGCACCUAUGAAGGAAAUACCUAUAACAGCUCCUUCAAAUGGCAGAGCCCGGCUGAGCCUUGUGUUCUACGCCAGUGCCAGGAGGGCGUUGUCACAGAGUCUGGGGUGCGCUGUGUUGUUCAUUGUAAAAACCCUUUGGAGCAUCUGGGAAUGUGCUGCCCCACAUGUCCAGGCUGUGUGUUUGAGGGUGUGCAGUAUCAAGAAGGGGAGGAAUUUCAGCCAGAAGGAAGCAAAUGUACCAAGUGUUCCUGCACUGGAGGCAGGACACAAUGUGUGAGAGAAGUCUGUCCCAUUCUCUCCUGUCCCCAGCACCUUAGUCACAUACCCCCAGGACAGUGCUGCCCCAAAUGUUUGGGUCAGAGGAAAGUGUUUGACCUCCCUUUUGGGAGCUGCCUCUUUCGAAGUGAUGUUUAUGACAAUGGAUCCUCAUUUCUGUACGAUAACUGCACAGCUUGUACCUGCAGGGACUCUACUGUGGUUUGCAAGAGGAAGUGCUCCCACCCUGGUGGCUGUGACCAAGGCCAGGAGGGCUGUUGUGAAGAGUGCCUCCUACGAGUGCCCCCAGAAGACAUCAAAGUAUGCAAAUUUGGCAACAAGAUUUUCCAGGAUGGAGAGAUGUGGUCCUCUAUCAAUUGUACCAUCUGUGCUUGUGUGAAAGGCAGGACGGAGUGUCGCAAUAAGCAGUGCAUUCCCAUCAGUAGCUGCCCACAGGGCAAAAUUCUCAACAGAAAAGGAUGCUGUCCUAUUUGCACUGAAAAGCCCGGCGUUUGCACGGUGUUUGGAGAUCCCCACUACAACACUUUUGACGGUCGGACAUUUAACUUUCAGGGGACGUGUCAGUACGUUUUGACAAAAGACUGCUCCUCCCCUGCCUCGCCCUUCCAGGUGCUGGUGAAGAACGACGCCCGCCGGACACGCUCCUUCUCGUGGACCAAGUCGGUGGAGCUGGUGCUGGGCGAGAGCAGGGUCAGCCUGCAGCAGCACCUCACCGUGCGCUGGAACGGCUCGCGCAUCGCGCUCCCCUGCCGCGCGCCACACUUCCACAUCGACCUGGAUGGCUACCUCUUGAAAGUGACCACCAAAGCAGGUUUGGAAAUAUCUUGGGAUGGAGACAGUUUUGUAGAAGUCAUGGCUGCGCCGCAUCUCAAGGGCAAGCUCUGUGGUCUUUGUGGCAACUACAAUGGACAUAAACGUGAUGACUUAAUUGGUGGAGAUGGAAACUUCAAGUUUGAUGUGGAUGACUUUGCUGAAUCUUGGAGGGUGGAGUCCAAUGAGUUCUGCAACAGACCUCAGAGAAAGCCAGUGCCUGAACUGUGUCAAGGGACAGUCAAGGUAAAGCUCCGGGCCCAUCGAGAAUGCCAAAAGCUCAAAUCCUGGGAGUUUCAGACCUGCCACUCGACUGUGGACUACGCCACUUUCUACCGGUCCUGUGUGACAGACAUGUGUGAAUGUCCAGUCCAUAAAAACUGUUAUUGCGAGUCAUUUUUGGCAUAUACCCGGGCCUGCCAGAGAGAGGGCAUCAAAGUCCACUGGGAGCCUCAGCAGAAUUGUGCAGCCACCCAGUGUAAGCAUGGUGCUGUGUACGAUACCUGUGGUCCGGGAUGUAUCAAGACGUGUGACAACUGGAAUGAAAUUGGUCCAUGCAACAAGCCGUGCGUUGCUGGGUGCCACUGUCCAGCAAACUUGGUCCUUCACAAGGGAAGGUGCAUCAAGCCAGUCCUUUGUCCCCAGCGGUGACCUUUGUUUCGAUCCUUAAGACUCUGAAAUCUGGUGACUUUGACACUGAAGCGGAAGAGCCAAUGAAGGACUGCAGUAUUUGUGUGCCCGAUUCUGUAAACACACACACACAGAGUAUAUAUGUGUAUAUAUAUAUAGAUAUAUUCAAAAACAUUGCAUCAUUUAUAUGAACUAUAGGGGGAUUAUUAUAUGUAUAUUUUUUGCUAUAAGACAUGUAUUGUUUCUAGGAUCCUAACCUGUAAGCCAUUGAACAUGUUGUAUAAAUACACCAGGUGUUUUUAAUUUAAUAAGGUGGCAUGCAGAUACAUUGGAUAGUGUUAACAUCACAUACAUUUGUCAUUUUUAAGGAAGUUUUCUAAGAGCCCUCAAUUGCCUGCCUGUAUUAAUUUUAGUUUUGAGUCAGGAUUUGUAAUGGAGUGGGAAAUGUGUUUCUCUGGAGAAGGGCACAUUUAUCUAGGGGCAUUUCAGGUUUCCAAAGAAAGGAAUGUAUGCCUGGGAAAGACAGCAGGAGAUUGGUGACCGGCCCUAAUGGUGCAUGAAAAGCGAGUGAUAGGCUGUUAGAAUGUAUUAGGUCAUGGGCUAACAUUAUUUCCAAAAUUGAUUGGCUGGUUGCCAAGAAAUAUAUAUUUGUCACUAGGGCAUAACCGAAGAAUCAAGUGAUUUCUUGCCAUCCUUGCGUAGUCCUCAAGUCUUCUAAUCAUCUAUGUGUGUAUGAUGGAUGUGACCAUUUAUAUGUCAUGUGUUGAAAUUAAAGGGUGUCUGGAUGCCAUGUUAAUUUUAUUGAGCAUGAGAAAGUAUUUGAAGAAACUGUUGCACAACAUAUGAUGAAAUUUUGAUUUCUCUGAAUCUCAGAGUAAUUUAAGAUGGGCAAAUCCAAUGAGUUGAUGUAACCCAUCUACAUUUUGUGGCUAUUUCAUGUAUAAAAUGAAAGGCUUUAGUUAUUUCUAGAGGAGUCCCAUCCAACACUAUUUGGCGACUGUUAAUAUGUUAUAAUUAUUAGACAGUGGAAAAGCCUUUAUUGACUAAUUGAUUUAACCUCAGUCCAAAGAACAGUCUCUAUACUUGCCCUCAUUUACUGAUAGGCUGCUACUAGUUACCAUUUGAUUGUCUUGACUUUCGUCUUCAGUUGAAUUGGUGAAAACAUCAACAAAAACAAAACCCACUGUGUCUUAAAAUAAAAUGUUCUGCAUUGUAGUCAAUAAAGGGCUUAAGAUGUAAAACAAUGCAUUUUCUCUCUCAAGAUGUCCUGUGUUAUACUUUACAAUUAGUUGUAUCAACUUCAGAUUCAUUAAAUUUUAACAGCUGUAUUUAGUUAUAAUUUUUGUAUCUUACAACAGUAUAUAUAAAGACUAUUAUUAAUAGACAAAAGCAAACCCACGUUUUUGACAAGCCAGCAUAUUGCCAAUGCUCGUCAAAGACAUUUAUGUUUCUUUUACAUUCAUGACAGCUAAAGUAUUAACUUGGAAUUUUUUUUUUUUUUUUUGACUGGAAAAUCCCUAGUUGUUUGAAUUAACUGAAUAAAGUGCAGGGCGUAAUAGUGACUGGCUGGGGGCACUGGGCCUUUGUGUUUUUUUUCAUUCCUGUGUUUGGAUACUAAUCACCCUCGUAUCUGCAGCCUGAGGUAGUCAGGUCAUUGUUUCAAUGCUGCCCUUGGAAAGAAGACUUUGACUUAGGUGCUUUGGGAUCUAAGUGUGGUUUGUGACUAUCCCCAUUAUUUAAGCAUUUGGGGGUCUCACUUUUGCUUAUCUGUAACACAAAGAGGCCAUGUAGUAUAGUGAGCAGGGUUGAGAAUCGGGAAAACUAGACCCCUGCCACUAACAGGCUAGGAGACUUUGGGCAGUAAUGGGAGGCACUGAGGGUUUGCAAAUACUUUCCUACUUGUAAUCUCAUUGAUUCCCUGCUCUGCCCUGACAGGAGGGGUAGGGAAAAUCAGUUGACGUUGCCUGGUGGUUCCUACCUUCUGUAAAACGAACAGAUUCCUUAAGAUUAGCUUUAAAUCCCUUUUCAGUUCACUGUUGGUUCUCAUCUUUGAAAGAGGGCAGCAUAAGGGAAAUGAUGGAGAAGGGAGAAUUGUGGAUGGUUAUUUAUAGCUCAUGAUUCAUCCAAGGACUGAGUUAUUCUCCCCAUGAGGCUAACCGGCCUCUUUCCCAACACUUAAUCAUGGCAGCCAGGAUGGGUGAAUGAUGAAAGCUCUUCUGCAUGAGCCGGUUUCAUCAUCUUGGGUGGGUUGAUUACAAGUUUGUGUGGCAUUCCUUUAGCUGGGGAUUAGCUUAAUCUCUGUACAUUUUUCUCAUUUCUAAUUGAAGAAGAAAGGGAGGGCAGAGAGGACAGAAAAUUACUUGGGUUUACUAAUUCAAAGAGCCAUCUCUGAUGGGAGAGGGUGAGGAAAUCAGCUGAAUGGUUGGCCUGCAUAUUCUUUUUUAGGCCACAGGCUACAGCUGAGCAAUGGCUUAGUCUAAUGAUUGGGCACAAUGAGGAUUUACCAAGUGCUUCAAUGAGAGCAGUCCUGUUUCAUUCACAUGGGAUGUUUUCAAUUGGUUCUUCAACUAAGCUCUUGCAGAGUGAGAUGACUUGAAAUAAAAAUGUUCUAUGAAUAUUGAAUUUGAUGAGAAACAAGCACCCUCAAUGAAGAACAAGCAUAAUUAUGAUUCUAAUUGCCCAUUGUUGGUACUCAGUAAAACUAAGUUCUUUCUUCUCUCCCUCUGUAAAUAGGAAUAUUUGAGGGUCCUGACCUAAAAUUUUUUAGCUGGGAAGAAAAGAUAUCUCUUUGGCAUCGACAAGAGCAAUUUUUGUUAAAACUGUGGUACACUAAGAAUCACUAACUCUUCAGGUUGAAGGCCUCACUCAUCUUAACUCGUUGACUGCUUCCUGACCAUCAGACCGUCCUGUAAGAGGGCAUCUUUCAAUAAGAACGAGAAAGACCCAGGAGGUUGACUAGCUUCUCCCAGCUUUCACUGAAACACGGAUAAACCAUUUCAACUGGAAAACUCUUCCUUUUUAUGAGAUAUUUCAGACACACAAAAAGGCAUAGAGAAAAAUGUUGCAAACAUCCAUGACUACAUUACCCUAAUUAAGAAACAUAACCUGGUAAGUAGUCAAUAAAUUUUUCUUGAAUCAAUAAAUAAAACCUAAUAAAUGCUGUCUCAUGGUUGCA